GACUUUGCUCCAGCAGCCUGUCCCAGUGAGGACAGGGACACAGUACUCGGCCACACCAUGGGGCGCCCACUGCACCUCGUCCUGCUCAGUGCCUCCCUGGCUGGCCUCCUGCUGCUCGGGGAAAGUCUGUUCAUCCGCAGGGAGCAGGCCAACAACAUCCUGGCGAGGGUCACGAGGGCCAAUUCCUUUCUUGAAGAGAUGAAGAAAGGACACCUCGAAAGAGAGUGCAUGGAAGAGACCUGCUCAUACGAAGAGGCCCGCGAGGUCUUUGAGGACAGCGACAAGACGAAUGAAUUCUGGAAUAAAUACAAAGAUGGCGACCAGUGUGAGACCAGUCCUUGCCAGAACCAGGGCAAAUGUAAAGACGGCCUCGGGGAAUACACCUGCACCUGUUUAGAAGGAUUCGAAGGCAAAAACUGUGAAUUAUUCACACGGAAGCUCUGCAGCCUGGACAACGGGGACUGUGACCAGUUCUGCCACGAGGAACAGAACUCUGUGGUGUGCUCCUGCGCCCGCGGGUACACCCUGGCUGACAACGGCAAGGCCUGCAUUCCCACAGGGCCCUACCCCUGUGGGAAACAGACCCUGGAACGCAGGAAGAGGUCAGUGGCCCAGGCCACCAGCAGCAGCGGGGAGGCCCCUGACAGCAUCACAUGGAAGCCAUAUGAUGCAGCCGACCUGGACCCCACCGAGAACCCCUUCGACCUGCUUGACUUCAACCAGACGCAGCCUGAGAGGGGCGACAACAACCUCACCAGGAUCGUGGGAGGCCAGGAAUGCAAGGACGGGGAGUGUCCCUGGCAGGCCCUGCUCAUCAAUGAGGAAAACGAGGGUUUCUGUGGUGGAACCAUUCUGAGCGAGUUCUACAUCCUAACGGCAGCCCACUGUCUCUACCAAGCCAAGAGAUUCAAGGUGAGGGUAGGGGACCGGAACACGGAGCAGGAGGAGGGCGGUGAGGCGGUGCACGAGGUGGAGGUGGUCAUCAAGCACAACCGGUUCACAAAGGAGACCUAUGACUUCGACAUCGCCGUGCUCCGGCUCAAGACCCCCAUCACCUUCCGCAUGAACGUGGCGCCUGCCUGCCUCCCCGAGCGUGACUGGGCCGAGUCCACGCUGAUGACGCAGAAGACGGGGAUUGUGAGCGGCUUCGGGCGCACCCACGAGAAGGGCCGGCAGUCCACCAGGCUCAAGAUGCUGGAGGUGCCCUACGUGGACCGCAACAGCUGCAAGCUGUCCAGCAGCUUCAUCAUCACCCAGAACAUGUUCUGUGCCGGCUACGACACCAAGCAGGAGGAUGCCUGCCAGGGGGACAGCGGGGGCCCGCACGUCACCCGCUUCAAGGACACCUACUUCGUGACAGGCAUCGUCAGCUGGGGAGAGGGCUGUGCCCGUAAGGGGAAGUACGGGAUCUACACCAAGGUCACCGCCUUCCUCAAGUGGAUCGACAGGUCCAUGAAAACCAGGGGCUUGCCCAAGGCCAAGAGCCAUGCCCCGGAGGUCAUAACGUCCUCUCCAUUAAAGUGAGAUCCCACUCAA